AUGUGCUUGUUCCAAAGGGGAAAAGAAGAGCGGGGAAGGAAAGGAGGAAAAACAACAACAACAAAAGCCACGACAGAGAACGGGAAAAGGCAGAGACUGAAAGCGAAGGACCGUCGGAGGAGGAGGGCGAGAGGUCUGGAGAGGAGGGCUCGCCGGAGGAGGCGGGCGGGGCGGGCUGUGCGGAGGGUGCGGCCAGCGCGGUACCCGCCCCGGCGAGGCGCUGGGGAGGCCCGGGUGGGGAGAAGAAAUGGGGCCUGGGGGACGGUAGGAGCCUCCGUGCGGAGACCACUGUUCAAGGCCACAGAUGGAAUCACUCAGUCCUGCUGCUACUGGAGAGGGAAGGUGACCUUGACGCUGCCUCCCGCUCGGCCUGGCCCCUCCGCCUGGCGUUUCAGGGCUGCACGGAGUAGGUCUGGCGGGCGGGGGGCGGGGCGCAGGCACCCGGGACGAGGGUUGCCAUGGGAACCGCUAGGGAGGCGUCCCCAGCCCGGGAGCCGGGAGGAGCUCGGUGGGAGGGGAGCGGGAGGCGGAGGGGGCUGCGCUGUCCGACGUGGGGAGACUGCGGCGGAGGGAGGAGGCGAGGGGCGGCAGGCACGGGCGGAAGUGACGGAAGCCAGGGCCCGAAGAUGGACGGAAUCUGUCGCCUCUGCACAGCCUCAUUCAGUUGUGUCCUUCCCAGACCCUCAGACUCGCCCACUACAGCGUCCAGCGCUGCCCGGGCGGGGGAGAAGGGGCGCCCUCCCGGGGGGGAUGGGUAGGGGGUGUCGGCCGGGGAAAUCAGGCCAUUUCCCGCCUCCCUUCCCCACCGGCACCCGCGCCACUCUUCCUGACAGGACCACCGAUGCCCUGCUCCACACCAACUGCGUCCUUUUCCCUAGAGAGAAACUGAGGCAGAGAGGGAGUUCCCUGCUCGCUCGGACACCCCAGCGCCCUCACAGAGACCCCUCGGACUCCCUGGGCCCCAGCCCCUCACGCAGCCCCUCAGACUCCUCACCGAAGCUGCCGUCACUCCCGCAGUUCCCCACCCCUCCCGUGGAAGACCCAUCCCUUAACCGAGCCUUCCUCUCCUCGCUGCACCGUCAGUCCCUUUUCCAGGUCUCCAUCCCCCUCAUGGAGCCCCACCCCAGCGUAGAAACCGCUUCUCCUCGCCGGGCCCCCGCCCUCUUCACAGGCUCCCAUCUGUCUCCGGGCUCCUACCGGGAAGUCCCCUCCCACUUGCCUUGAGAGCCGCUAAUCCCUCUGGAGUCCUCACAUCUCACUCAGUCCCCAUCCUCUUUUCAUCCUCUUUUCCUCUUUGAGUCCCUACCCAUCCCUGGUACGGGAUCAGCCCUUGUACCUUGAGAAGGGAGUUUGGGUGGAGGACUCGGGGUUGGGAGAGAAGUGACCUCCACUUUGGAAGGAGCUAAUGACAGCCUCCCUUGUUGUUUCCUCCCCUAGCCCCAGUUCUGCCCUGGGCAAUGCGUGCCCACUGCCCAUCUCCCUGGAGAGCCAGCCUGUGCCAGGCAGCUGCAUCUGCCUCCCACCCUGUCAUGAGCUGUCAGCCUUGAUUUUGUCCCACAUUUGCUGUGUGAUCUUGGGAAAGUCAUUGUGCCCCUCCAACCGUCAUCAAGCACCCUUGCACAGACA